AGUUUUGUUUCUUUUCCAGGCACCCAGCAACGGCGGCCUCCAGGCCUCAGGCCCCCUCACCAUCCUAGAGGUCAAGAUCAGCUCUGGCUAGUUCUCACAGGUCUGACCCAACAAGUAGCACUGACAUUUUUACGUUUGCUGGAUGUACACACGGAAGUGGAGGAGGAGGAGGAGAAGGAGGAGGGCAGCUCCUUAGCUCAAGAGCAAGUGGCCCAAGGCCUCAGAAGACUAGAAGGAAGUUCCUGGCCAUUCAGCAUGGUUUCCCACGGGUCCUCGCCCUCCCUCCUGGAGGCCCUGAGCAGCGACUUCCUGGCCUGUAAAAUCUGCCUGGAGCAGCUGCGGGCACCCAAGACACUGCCCUGCCUGCAUACCUACUGCCAAGACUGCCUGGCACAGCUGGCGGAUGGCGGCCGCGUCCGCUGCCCCGAGUGCCGCGAGACAGUGCCUGUGCCGCCCGAGGGUGUGGCCUCCUUCAAGACCAACUUCUUCGUCAAUGGGCUGCUGGACCUGGUGAAGGCCCGGGCCUGUGGAGACCUGCGUGCCGGGAAGCCAGCCUGUGCCCUGUGUCCCCUGGUGGGUGGCACCAGCACCGGGGGGCCGGCCACGGCCCGGUGCCUGGACUGUGCCGAUGACUUGUGCCAGGCCUGUGCCGACGGGCACCGCUGCACCCGCCAGACCCACACCCACCGCGUGGUGGACCUGGUGGGCUACAGGGCCGGGUGGUAUGAUGAGGAGGCCCGGGAGCGCCAAGCGGCCCAGUGUCCCCAGCACCCCGGGGAGGCACUGCGCUUCCUGUGCCAGCCCUGCUCACAGUUGCUGUGCAGAGAGUGCCGCCUAGACCCCCACCUGGACCACCCCUGCCUGCCUCUGGCUGAAGCUGUGCGUGCCCGGAGGCCGGGCCUGGAGGGACUGCUGGCCGGUGUGGACAAUAACCUGGUGGAGCUGGAGGCAGCGCGGAGGGUGGAGAAGGAGGCGCUAGCCCGGCUGCGGGAGCAGGCGGCCCGGGUGGGGACUCAGGUGGAGGAGGCGGCUGAGGGCGUCCUCCGGGCCCUGCUGGCCCAGAAGCAGGAGGUGCUGGGGCAGCUACGAGCCCACGUGGAGGCUGCCGAAGAAGCUGCUCGGGAGAGGCUGGCGGAGCUUGAGGGCCGGGAGCAGGUGGCCAGGGCCGCAGCCGCCUUCGCCCGCCGGGUACUCAGCCUGGGGCGAGAGGCCGAGAUCCUCUCCCUGGAAGGGGCGAUCGCACAGCGGCUCAGGCAGCUGCAGGGCUGCCCCUGGGCACCAGGCCCGGCCCCCUGCCUGCUCCCACAGCUGGAGCUCCAUCCUGGGCUCCUGGACAAGAACUGCCACCUUCUUCGGCUGUCCUUUGAGGAGCAGCAGCCCCAGAAGGAUGGUGGGAAAGACGGAGCUGGUACCCAGGGAGGUGAGGAGAGCCAGAGCCGGAGGGAGGAUGAGCCGAAGACUGAGAGACAGGGUGGAGUCCAGCCCCAGGCUGGAGAUGGAGCCCAGACCCCAAAAGAGGAAAAAGCCCAGACAACCCGAGAAGAGGGAGCCCAGACCUUGGAGGAGGACAGGGCCCAGACACCCCACGAGGAUGGAGGACCCCAGCCCCACAGGGGUGGCAGACCCAACAAGAAGAAAAAGUUCAAAGGCAGGCUCAAGUCAAUUUCCCGGGAGCCCAGCCCAGCCCUGGGGCCGAAUCUGGACGGCUCUGGCCUCCUCCCCAGACCCAUCUUUUACUGCAGUUUCCCCACGCGGAUGCCUGGAGACAAGCGGUCCCCCCGGAUCACCGGGCUCUGUCCCUUCGGUCCCCGGGAGAUCCUGGUGGCGGAUGAGCAGAACCGGGCACUGAAACGCUUCUCCCUCAACGGCGACUACAAGGGCACCGUGCCGGUCCCUGAGGGCUGCUCCCCUUGCAGCGUGGCCGCCCUGCAGAGCGCGGUGGCCUUCUCCGCUAGCGCACGGCUCUAUCUCAUCAACCCCAACGGCGAAGUGCAGUGGCGCAGGGCCCUGAGCCUCUCCCAGGCCAGCCACGCGGUGGCGGCACUGCCUAGCGGGGACCGCGUGGCUGUCAGCGUGGCGGGCCACGUGGAGGUGUACAAUAUGGAAGGCAGCCUGGCCACCCGGUUCAUUCCUGGAGGCAAGGCCAGCCGGGGCCUGCGGGCGCUGGUGUUUCUGACCACCAGCCCCCAGGGGCAUUUCGUGGGGUCGGACUGGCAGCAGAAUAGUGUGGUAAUCUGUGAUGGGCUGGGCCAGGUGGUUGGGGAGUACAAGGGGCCAGGCCUGCAUGGCUGCCAGCCGGGCUCCGUGUCUGUGGAUAAGAAGGGCUACAUCUUUCUGACCCUUCGAGAAGUCAACAAGGUGGUGAUCCUGGACCCGAAGGGGUCCCUCCUUGGAGACUUCCUGACAGCCUACCACGGCCUGGAAAAGCCCCGGGUUACCACCAUGGUGGAUGGCAGGUACCUGGUCGUGUCCCUCAGUAACGGGACCAUCCACAUCUUUCGGGUCCGUUCUCCGGACAGUUAAAGGGGCUAGGACUAGGGUGAGAGGGAGUGGGGAGGGAGAGGGCAGGAAGGAGGCAGAGCUGUCCGUGGGAGGUGGAGGCCGAGGACAUUUUCCUGAAGGGCAGGGGUUGGCAACUUUUCAACAUGGAGUGCCAAACUGCUAACCCGUCUUCUAGUGUGUGAGAAUAGGGACCAAGGUGGUGGCGUGACCUUAACUCUCAGAAGCAGAGGAGGCAGGUGGGUGGAGGGGGAUGCUGGGAGUUCACCUGCCUCUUGCUUUUUGUGGGUGGCUGCUGCCACCACCGCCGCUGCUAUAUAGUUUAGGUUUCUGAGGUUUGUGAGCCUGUCCUGCUUUGCAUUCUUCAAAACCAUUCCUGAUAGAGUAGCCGAGGGAGAGUCUUGGGGCCAAGAAGGGCCCAGGGUGGGUCAGGCGUGUGCACUGUGGAACAGAGCUGAGACCCCGGCCCCCCUUGGACUGGCACAGGGUCCUACAGAGUCAGAGGAGGCCUGAGAUUUCGAAUGGGCAGUGAAUGGCCUCUUCUGCCAGCCACAGGCAGGAUGCUCCUUGAUCACGGCAUCCCCCGGCGGUAGUACAGGGUGAGCUUGCAGGAGGGUCUGCAAGUGCAGACAGCAGCUGGGGCCAAAGAGGUGUUAGGUUCAAAGGCUGCGAAGAGAAUAGGCUACUGGAAAACCAAACCCAACAGAAUUCACGUCCAAAAAUCCACAUUCUCCAUCGCUUCUCAGCCUUUUGGCUAAGAUUAAGUAUUAAAAAAAAACCAGGCUCUGCCAGGCGCAGUGGCUCAUGCCUAUAAUCCCGGCACUUUGGGAGUCUGUGGCAGGAGGAUUGCUUGAGGCCAGGAGUUUGAGACCAGCCUGGGCAACAUAGCGAGACCCCAUCUCUACAAAAGAUUAAAAAUUAGCUGCGUGUAGUAGCAUAUGCCUUUCAACGUAGCUACUCAGGAGGCUGAGGUGGGAGGAUCCCUUGAGCCGAGGAGUUUGAGUCUGCAGUGAGCUAUGAUCGCACCACUGCAUUCCAGACCCCAUCUCGAAAAAAAAAAAAAAAAAAAAAAACAGAAACAACAGAAAAAGCAGGUUAUCCAUCACUUCUCAGCUAAGAUCAAGUGUUAAAAUAAAUAAAUAAAUAAAUAAAUAAAUAAAUAAAUAAAUACCAAGUUAUGAGUGUCAGAGCAGGGGAGCCCUCCACGCAGCCACGGAGCCAGUCUGAGGGAAGAGGUACAUAGGAUAGAAAAAUCUCUAGGCUCCAACGCUUCUGCUUCGGUGUCUUUCCAUUUCCCAGGGUCUAUGUGUUGCCUUCUCUUCAUUUUCCAGCAAAAUUCCUUUUGAGAUAUGUUGGCCUUCACUCGGCUGAACUAGGGGGUGAAGGAAGGUUGUCCUCUGUGGGCCACUAUUGCUGGGGAAACAGCUAAACCCUGCAGGCCAAGUGGAACUUGGAGGUGCCAAGAAAACCUAGAAGGUGCAAUGGGGCUGCGACGGAUAGAGGUGUCAAACCAGAAGGGAGGAACCCGUCGGAGGUGGGCUGUGACCACCGGACCUUUUCAUAAGUGGUGGCAGUGGUAGAAUUGAGGGGGCAAGUAGGCUUGGAGAAUGUUUUUAGCCAGGGGCUGUUGAGAGAUGGCAGAAGGGGGUCUUAAUGUGGGGACUGUGGACAGUGGGGCAUUCGUGGGAACCAGAGGGAUUUUGGACAAGUCCAGAUGGAAUGUGCAGGGCAUAGGUAGAGGGAAAAGAAAAUCCCUUUCUGGGAAAACCAUUUCUUGUUUAUUGAAACAAUGCAGGACAUCAUCAAAGUCCGGGUGGACACAUUCCAUUAUCUACAAAUUACAAAGGUAGGCACAGCAAAGAAUAAUGAAGAUUAUAAGAAAACCAAGCGCCAGGCACGGUGACUCAAGCCUGUAAUCCCAGCACUCUGGGAGGCUGGGGUGGGUGGAUCACUCAAGGUCAGGAGUUCGAGACCAGCCUGGCCAACAUGGAGAAACCCCAUCUCUACUAAAAAUACAAAAAUUAGCUAGGCGUGGGAGCGGGCGUCUGUAAUCCCAGCUACUUGGGAGGCUGAGGCAGGAGAAUCAUUUGAACCCAGGAGGUGGAAGUUGCAGUGAGCUCAGAUCGCACCAUUGCACUCCAGCCUGGGUAACAAGAAUGAAACUCCAUCUCAAAAAAAAAGAAAAAGAAAAGAAAGAAAACCAAGGUCCCUCUCCCUCUCCCUCUCCCCACGGUCUCCCUCUGCCUCUCUUUCCAUGGUCACGGUCUCCCUCUGAUGCCGAGCCGAAGCUGGACUGUACUGCUGCCAUCUCGGCUCACUGCAACCUCCCUGCCUGAUUCUCCUGCCUCAGCCUGCCGAGUGCCUGCGAUUGCAGGCGCGCGCCGCCACGCCUGACUGGUUUUCGUAUUUUUUUGGUGGAGACGGGGUUUCACUGUGUUGGCCGGGCUGGUCUCCAGCUCCUAACCGCGAGUGAUCCGCCAGCCUCGGCCUCCGGAGGUGCCGGGAUUGCAGACGGAGUCUCGUUCACUCGGUGCUCAAUGUUGCCCAGGCUGGAGUGCAGUGUCGUGAUCUCGGCUAGCUACAACCUCCACCUCCCAGCCGCCCGCCUUGGCCUCCCAAAGUGCCGAGAUUACAGCCUCUGCCCGGCCGCCACCCCCUCUGGGAAGUGCGGAGUGUCUCUGCCUGGCCGCCCAUUGUCUGGGAUGUGAGGAGCCCCUCUGCCCGGCUGCCCAGUCUGGGAAGUGAGGAGCGCCUCUUCCUGGCCGCCAUCCCAUCUAGGAAGUGAGGAGUGUCUCUGCCCGGCUGCCCAUCAUCUGAGAUGUGGGGAGCACCUCAGCCCCGCCGCCCCGUCUGGGAUGUGAGGAGCGCCUCUGCCCGGCCGCGACCCAGUCUGGGAGGUGAGGAGCGUCUCUGCCCAGCCGCCCCGUCUGAGAAGUGAGGAGCCCCUCCGCCUGGCAGCCGCCCCGUCUGAGAAGUGAGGAGCCCCUCCGCCCGGCAGCCGCCCCGUCCGGGAGGGAGGUGGGGGGUCAGCCCCCUCCCGGCCAGCCGCGCCGUCCGGGAGGGAGGUGGGGGGUCAGCCCCCGCCCGGCCAGCCGCGCCUUCCGGGAGGGAGGUGGGGGAUCAGUCCCCGCCCGGCCAGCCGCCCCGCCCGGGAGCGAGGUGGGGGGCGCCUCCGCCCGGCCGCUGUCCCGUCCGGGAGGUGGGGGGUCGCCUCUGCCCGGCCGCCCCGUCUGGGAGGUGAGGAGCCCCUCUGCCCGGCCACCACCCCGUCUGGGAGGUGUACCCAACAGCUCAUUGAGAACGGGCCAUGAUGACGAUGGCGGUUUUGUGGAAUAGAAAAGGGGGAAAGGUGGGGAAAAGAUAGAGAAAUCAGAUUGUUGCCGUGUCUGUGUAGAAAGAAGUAGACAUGGGAGACUUCAUUUUGUUCUGUACUAAGAAAAAUUCUUCUGCCUUGGGAUGCUGUUAAUCUAAGACCUUACCCCCAACCCCGUGCUCUCUGAAAUAUGUGCUGUGUCCACUCAGGGUUAAAUGGAUUAAGGGCGGUGCAAGAUGUGCUUUGUUAAACAGAUGCUUGAAGGCAGCAUGCUCCUUAAGAGUCAUCACCACUCCCUAAUCUCAAGUACCCAGGGACACAAACACUGCGGAAGGCCGCAGGGUCGUCUGCCUAGGAAAACCAGAGACCUUUGUUCACUUGUUUAUCUGCUGACCUUCCCUCCACUAUUGUCCUAUGACCCUGCCAAAUCCCCCUCUGCGAGAAACACCCAAGAAUGAUCAAUAAAAAAUUAAAAAAAAAAAAAAAAAAAGAAAACCAAGAAGAUGGGAAAACCAUGCAGAAUUGAUUUGACGAGGAAAGCCUUGGUCUCUAAUACAUGCAAUGACUAGAACAGUAUUUGGUCAAAGAACCACAUAAGCUCUGUACCCUGGAGGAAAUGUAUGCAGGCAAGGACUAGUAAAAUAAAAAAUAAUAAUAAUUAAAAAAAAAAAAAAGAAAGGCUGGACGCGGUGGCUCACACCUGUAAUCCCAGCACUUUGGGAGGCUGAGGUGGGUGGAUCACCUGAGGUCAGGAGUUUGAGACCAGCCUGGCCACUACGGUGAAACCCCAUCUCUACUAAAAAUACAAAAAUUACCCGGGUGUGGUGGCGCAUGCCUGUAAUCCCAGCUACUGGGGAGUCUGAGGCAGGAGACUCGCUUGAACCUGGGAGGCAGAGGGUGCAGCGAGCCGAGUUCACCCCAUUGCACUCCAGCCUGGGUGUCACAGUGAGACUCUGUCUCAAAAAAAUAAUAAAUAAAUAAUUAAAUCCACUUGCAGUGGUCAAAAAUAAAUGUUAAAUAAAUGGGUGAGAAAUCUUGCGGAGAAAUAGACUCCUGGCACUAUAAAAAUGAUCCUGGAGAAUAAUUUGGCUAGACUUUGCAAGAAUGACAAAAAUGAUUAUAAGAAUCAGUUGUCUCACUUUGGGGAAUACAUUCUGGGAAAAUAAUGUAAGAGAAAAAAUAUUUGCAUACAGACAUUUGAGGCUGCUCUGUAUAUUACAGGCAAGAACUGGAAACUGUUCGGCUGCAGGGUGACAGCUAACUAGAUUGUGGUUUAUUAGGGGAAUGAGCCUUUCUUUGUGUAUGACAACUAUGAAAACUAUUGAGAAGAAAUAGUUACGUGAUACAGUCAUAAUCCUCAAAAACGGAGAAUCAGGAAUUAUGAUCAAAUAGUGAUAGUAACAAGGAAAACAUCUGUCUAAAUAAUUACUGAGUAGAAAUAGGUUCGGAAUUUGUAAAUAGUCAUUAAUUUGGGAGAUUGGGGUUUUUUUUGUUUUGUUUUUUGUUUGUUUUUCAUUAUUUUGUGCUAUUAUUCAUACGUGUACAUUUCUACUUCAGUUUUUAUUAUCCAUUACAUAACAUACAUGCUUGAUUAUUUGCUUCAAGGAAAUACACCUUUAUAAGUAAUACUCAAUAACUACUGGGUUUGAGAAUGAAGGUGUCAGAACGAAUGAGAUUGUCCUAUGAAAGAAGAGGCAGGAGCCAGGGAGGAGGAUCCCACCCGGCCGGGGCUCAGCCAGGAGGCAGGGCCAUUGGGGCAGGGUGGCAGUCCAAGGAACCGCUCUGGGAAGGUUUGCAAAGGUCGGGGUCCCCCCUGCCAGGUGAUCGAAUUAUCGUGGAGUGUCUGGAAGGCGGGGGAAGUUUUGUUGAGUUCACCAAAUAACUCAGACCAACUGGAAACCAAGUGGAGUUUCUACAGGACCAACUAGAAUAGGGAUCAGCUACAUGGGGGCGGGGGGAGGGGGGCAGGGAACGGUGUCUGUCUUCAUUGCAGCUCUGUCUGCAGAGCCAGCACUGUGAUACCUCAUAGUAGGUGCUCAGUGAAUGUCUGUGAAGUGAAUUACUAUCUAGACAAGGAUGAGACUGGUAUGACUCUCCAAAGCUUUCCCACCUCCAAAACCUCGGCUUGUGGGGAAUCUCCAGUAGGGGGCACUGUGGACACGGUUCGCAUCUGCCUCCCAAGGCUGGGCUCCGCGUCAAAAAAAAAAAAAAAAAAUGAGACUGAGCCAGGUGCAGUGGUCACUCCUGUUAUCUCAGCACUUUGCGUGGCCAAGGCGGGAGGAUGUCUUGAGGCCAGGAGUUCAAGACUAGGCUGGGCAACAUAGCAAGACCCCAUCUCUACAAAAAAAUUUUUAAAUUAGCCAGAGGUGGUGGCAUGCACCCGUAGUCCCAGCUGCUCGGGAGGCUGAGGCAGAAGAUUGCUCGAGCCCAGGAGUUCAAGGCUGCAGUGAGCUCUGAUUGUGCCACUGCACUCCAGCCUGAGUGACAGAGCAAAACCUGGUUUCCUAAGGGGGGGAUAAAAGAGGGAGAGAUGAGAUCGGGGUGUCCCGCUUCUGUGCAUGUGGAGGGGGUAACUGGGAACCGUGUACUGUAGGGGAUCGCACACCUUGGGGUGGAAACAGCAGCUCUCCGGAGUUGCAUGGGAGCCAUGGGCAGUGGUCCUGGCUGGUGAAAUGAUUCUAGCCACGUGGCCCACCCAGGGGGCAAAACAAUAGAAACCUUCAGAAAUGAAACGUCACCUGGCUGCAAGAAGAUAGUCCCACAGGCGCCCUAGAGAUGGGGAUGCCAAGUGGCUUCUCGGGAAGCUGUAAGAAUCCACAGGGCAUUGUAAGAUGGAGGGAAAUAUUAAGUUUUCUUCGUAAAGAGGUGAGGGGGGCGAGAGCAGCAAAGGACACUGGAAAAUGAGAAGCAUGGAUGGGAAGUGUUGCAUUGAGCAUAAUUUGGAGGUAAAAUCUCCAACACCGUAACUGAGUGGCCUGGGGACCUGAUAGAAAGCCCUGCUCAGGACUAAGGCAGAGUUCCCAGUUAUAUCGCAGAUACAAAGAGACCAGGAACACGCUUGUAAUCACAGCACUUAGGGAGGCUGAGGCGGGUGGAUGACCUGAGGUCAGGAGUUCGAGACCAGCCUAGCCAACAUGGUGAAACCCCCAUCUCUACUAAAAAUACAAAAAUUAGCCAGGCGUGGUGGCACAUGCCUGUAAUCCCAGCUACUCAGGAGGCUGAGGUGGGAGAAUCGCUUGAGCCCGGGAGGCAGGGGUUGCAGCGAGCUGAGAUCGUACCACUGCACUCCAGCCUGGGCAACAGAGUGAGACCCUGUCUCAAAAAGAAAAAAAAAAAAGAGAGAAAUCAGGAACAUCAUGAAAGAUACAGCAAAAUGUUUUACCCCAGCCCACUGCACCACACCUGGGAUUGUGACAAUUAACUUGAUAAAUUGUUCCUUUUCCUGUUCGGAACUGACUAGGUUGUGCGUGGAUGGACCAGUGAAAAGAAAAUCCUGUUUGGGUAGGGAAGAGGGAAGUAGAAAACCUCUUUCGUAUUCUUGGUGUCAAGAAAUGGGAAGAGAAUGAGGGAGCAGAGACCUGGGUUGAGUGUUGGCUCUGCACUAAACAGCUGUGUGAUCUUGGUCUAGUGCCUUAACCUCUCUGAGCCUCAGUUUGUACAUCAGUAACAUUGGGAUAAUGACAUCCACAUGCCCACUUCACAGAGCUGCUGUGAGGACUGGAUGAGAAAUGUAGAGAAGUAUUUCGGACACCAUAAAGCUCAAAUACAAGGUGUUGGUUAGGAAAAGUUUCAACUGACUUGUACCCACCUGAUACCCCUCCAUCAGCAUAAGCGUGUAUGAGGAUGUUAGGUACAUGUGUUGUGAGUGAAAGCUCUGGAACACCCGAGUAGAGCUUUCUGCAAAUCAGCUUCUCCUUCAGAGGAGACCAUUUUGUUUUGCUUUCCAGCAGUUACUUGAAGAAGCCUUAUCUGAAGUCACAACAGUGACUUCAGGAAUAGAAGGGACCAAUGGCCAGCUUGCUGAAAUGUAAUGCCAUUCUUAAAAGCCAGCUAAGAAUCAGACCGUAUUAGUUAAGGACCCAUAAGAGUAGACAUUUAGAAAAAGUGAAAAAUGGCAAGAGUGGCCCAAUCUUUUGAGAGUUUAGAGAAAAUAUCAUUUGGAAAGGGAGUAGCUCUCCUUCUAUUUUAGCCUUAUUAUUACGGUAUCUAUAAAGCAAUGCCAUAUUCUAAAUCUGCAGAAAUAAAAUUCUAAGGGGCGAAAGUCCAAGGCAGAAGUCAAAAGUUUUGCAAGGAAACCGAUGAGGUUGCUGACCUGAGCUGGGCAGGGUUGAACAGGCGAGUGCCAAGAUCAAGGUCUCUGAUUGUCUCUCCUUGAAAGGUAAGCAGAGAACUAGGGCUAUCCCAUAAAUUAAGUGGGAGAUUGGAAAGGGGUGCGGACUUCUGUAUUGGGGAGAAGGUCUUGGAUGAACUGGGGCAGAGAACUGCCAGAGAGAGUACCUAGGAAUACGUUGUUAGCAGGAGAAAGACCAAGUUCAGAUGCAGACUUGGGAAAGUAGGUAACUUGACCAAAGGUAGCAAAAUUAGACUACCCAACUGGAUUGUGAAUGCAGUUUAUGAAAUGGAUCAGGACAGGAGCAAAAAUAGAUUUUCUAGAAACUGCAGACUCCUGUGAUUGGAGCAGUAUACAAAGUACAGCAACAUCAGACUAGAUCUCACCUGAGGUGCUGGGUGAGAAAUCUUAGGGACCAGAUGGAAGAGGGCCUGUGUAUAAAGACAUUAGGAAGGAGGUUUGGGAGGGCAGCCUGACUUGUCUCCAGAGAAAGUUAGAACUGGUUGACUUAGCAACCAAGGGACACUGGGUCAAAGACGAGGAAUCAGGACGUCGGUGCCUAGUGACUGAGCGCCAGCCCAGCCCAUUUCUCUACAUUGCCAUGGGCUAAACCCAGUGUGCUGUAAACUCUUCAGUUCCUUUGGUUAUGGAUUUUGUAUCUUUUCUGUGUUUCUUAAUAAAGUUCUUUUGAAAAAUGGGAACCUUUCUCAGAUGGGAAUUUUGUAUCUUUCCUCUGUUUCUUAAUAAAGUUCUUUUGAAAAAUUGGAA